UGACAGCUUAAUUUAUAAUUUCGUUUAGAAAUCAAAGAAAUGCUACAGUGACUGUCAGUGUACUGAUUAUUUAAAAGAAUAUGAGGAACUGCAUUAAAUUUGGUACUCAUCAUAUUGGGGGAAUCACGGACAUUAGGAGGUAGCACAGCAGAAAGCACCAUGUAAAUGUCUACCAUAACUAACAAAUAUUGUUUUCACUGCAUCUAAGAGAUGAAUCGGUGUAUGUGAAAAAGUAAUUCAGUGUCAAAUAAAGGGAAAUACUGAUGGACAGGAUCUGUAAAAUCAGAAAUAAUUUCUAAUGUGAUUUUAAGUAUUUUGGUUGCUCUUUUUUAUUCUGUUUUUUUUCAGAUACUUUGUUUUUUUUUUUUUUUGUCCUGUUUAAAUGAAUGUUUAAUGACAUGACAACGCUUUCCCCAAAUCCAAACAGUAAAAAAAACUCUGCGUUGAAACUGCUGGUUAAGCAGUCGUCCAGCAAGUUAAUGAAAUGACAGAAUCCUACAGUUGAGUACAUGAAUUCCAUAUACAACCCAGUGCCUUGGGAGAAAGAAGAGUAUUUGAAGCCAGUAUUAGAAGAUGACCUUUUACUUCAAUUUGAUGUAGAAGAUCUUUAUGAACCGGUGUCAGUACCCUUCUCAUACCCCAAUGGACUCAGUGAAAAUACAUCUGUUGUUGAAAAAUUGAAACAUAUGGAAGCCAGGGCACUGUCUGCUGAAGCCGCAUUGGCCAGAGCACGUGAGGAUCUGCAAAAAAUGAAACAAUUUGCUCAGGAUUUUGUGAUGCACACAGAUGUCAGAACCUGCUCGUCAUCUACUAGUGUCAUUGCGGACCUCCAGGAGGAUGAGGAUGGUGUUUAUUUCAGCUCAUACGGGCAUUAUGGGAUACAUGAAGAAAUGCUAAAGGACAAAAUACGAACAGAAAGCUACCGAGAUUUCAUAUACCAAAAUCCACAUAUCUUCAAAGACAAGGUAGUUUUGGAUGUUGGGUGUGGAACUGGAAUUCUCUCUAUGUUUGCUGCUAAAGCUGGGGCGAAGAAGGUUCUUGGAGUUGAUCAAUCUGAAAUACUUUACCAGGCAAUGGAUAUUAUAAGACUAAAUAAACUUGAAGAUACUAUUACACUAAUUAAAGGAAAGAUUGAAGAAGUUCAUCUUCCUGUAGAAAAAGUAGAUGUUAUCAUAUCUGAGUGGAUGGGCUAUUUUCUUCUGUUUGAGUCUAUGUUAGAUUCUGUCCUUUAUGCAAAGAACAAAUACUUGGCAAAAGGAGGCUCGGUCUACCCUGACAUUUGCACUAUCAGCCUUGUAGCAGUGAGUGAUGUGAAUAAACAUGCUGAUAGAAUUGCUUUUUGGGAUGAUGUCUAUGGCUUCAAGAUGUCCUGCAUGAAGAAAGCAGUUAUUCCAGAAGCUGUUGUGGAAGUUUUAGAUCCGAAGACUCUUAUUUCAGAACCUUGUGGUAUUAAGCAUAUAGAUUGCCAUACGACGUCUAUCUCAGAUUUGGAAUUUUCAUCAGAUUUUACCCUGAAAAUCACAAGGACAUCCAUGUGCACGGCAAUUGCUGGCUACUUUGAUAUAUAUUUUGAGAAGAAUUGCCACAACAGGGUCGUGUUCUCUACGGGCCCUCAGAGCACCAAAACACACUGGAAACAAACAGUAUUUCUACUGGAAAAACCAUUUUCAGUUAAAGCAGGUGAAGCCUUGAAAGGAAAGGUCACAGUUCACAAGAAUAAGAAAGAUCCACGUUCUCUCACCGUGACCCUCACGUUGAAUAAUUCAACUCAAACUUAUGGUCUCCAGUGAAACAGCCAUAAAAGCACACUACCUUGUAGUUUUUAAUGUGGGGGUAGAGUGGGUCAGCAGGAGGGAGCUGGUUUUAUGUGAGCAGAUGGAUGGAUGAUGGACCCUUUCCUAAUGAGCCUCCUCAAUAAGAGAGAAGUUCUCAUUGUGGGAAUCUGACAUAGUUCAGCUGAGGAAGAGAAUCAGCUGAUCCUCAUGGUCUGCCACGUAAUCAUUUUCUUAGACGUUUGCUCCACCAGAUUUAACCAAAUGUAACUCCCACAUUGAGUUUAUCUAUAUUGAAAAUCAUUUACAUUGGCCUAUAUUUGGAAGAGAGAUAGUCUUUUGUUUUUAAUAAGUUUCUUACUAUAAAUUUUAAACAAAUUGGUUAGUUAUUUGGAUAUUUUAUUAAACUAGUAACACAGGUACUACACAUUUUAUUAUGGACUCCUCUGAGGAGGAGUUUUUAAUUGUAUUUGCUAGAAAAUCAGGAUGUAAUAAAGAUUUGUAUAAAAAAACUAAAAUAUGGAAAAGAGCUUCAGCCUUCAUAUACAAAUCAUAUAUGCAGACAGCCUAGUUGAUUAUCUAGCAUACUUAGGGUUCUCAUUUUGUAGUUUCUUCCCUCUUUGUGACUAUUCCUUAGCCUUAUAGAUUUCUAGUACUGCCCAGGAAAUCUAAUUUCAAUACAUUUAUCCUAGGUUUCAUGAAAGUUUUUAAAGAUUGGGAUAAAUAUGUACUUAUUUACUAACGUAUUAUCUUUUUCAAACCAGAUUUAUGUGCAAAGGUUAAACAUGUAACUGUUACUAAGCAGUCUAUAAAGUUGUCAUUUACAAUUACUGAUUCAAUUUGAAAUGUAGAAUAAAAUUUUAAUAAAAUGUAUCAACUUAUAAAAUAUUUUAAAAAUAUUGAUAUUAUAAAAGUUUUCAAUAAAAUAUAUCAAACAACAUUA